AACAUAGCCAUUGCUCUGACAGUGUUGUGAAGGGAGCAGAAGAGGAGAAACCUAAUCUCCGAACCCAACAACACCUAGCAACAGUAGAAAAAACUUUUAAACAAAAGUCUGGGUGGGAGAUAUACAACAACUUCCAAUUUCUGCUGAUCGGGAUUUCAGGGAGAAGAAGCUGCUUUCCCUCCUCUCUACUCUGUUUCCUGCAUGACUUCAGCUAUUGGCUGGUCCUGGGAAAGAAAGUGGGAAAAGCUUUUUCCUCUGUAUUCUUUUGGGCUGGAUAGUUUUUGAGAACUCGAAUCUGUCUUGGGCUGUGAGACAAGCCACUGGGUUCUUCAAAGGAUAAACUACCUACAUAGAGGACAUACCUUUGGUUAAAGGAGCUGCCGUCAGGUGGGAAUGAGAUCUCGAAACCAAGGUGGUGAAAGUGCAUCUGAUGGGCAUAUCUCCUGUCCCAAGCCCUCCAUCAUCGGCAAUGCUGGUGAAAAAAGUCUCUCAGAAGAUGCAAAAAAGAAGAAGAAAUCAAAUAGGAAGGAGGAUGAUGUCAUGGCCUCAGGAACUGUCAAACGACACCUAAAAACAUCUGGAGAAUGUGAACGAAAAACUAAGAAAUCCCUGGAGUUAUCCAAAGAAGACCUCAUCCAACUACUCAGUAUAAUGGAAGGGGAGUUGCAGGCCAGAGAAGAUGUGAUCCACAUGCUGAAGACAGAGAAAACCAAGCCUGAGGUUCUGGAGGCUCAUUACGGGUCUGCGGAGCCAGAGAAAGUGCUGCGGGUCCUGCACCGAGAUGCCAUUCUUGCCCAGGAGAAAUCCAUAGGAGAAGAUGUCUAUGAGAAACCGAUUUCAGAGCUGGACAGACUUGAGGAAAAACAGAAAGAAACCUACCGGCGCAUGCUAGAGCAGCUGUUGCUGGCCGAGAAGUGUCAUAGGCGCACCGUAUACGAGUUAGAGAACGAGAAGCAUAAACACACUGACUACAUGAACAAGAGCGACGACUUCACCAACCUGCUGGAGCAGGAGCGGGAGAGGUUAAAAAAGCUCCUUGAACAAGAAAAGGCUUAUCAAGCCCGCAAAGAAAAGGAAAAUGCUAAACGACUCAAUAAACUAAGAGAUGAGCUUGUUAAACUCAAAUCCUUUGCACUCAUGCUGGUGGAUGAAAGACAAAUGCACAUUGAACAACUUGGCCUGCAAAGCCAGAAAGUACAGGAUCUUACUCAGAAGCUGAGGGAAGAAGAAGAGAAGCUCAAAGCCAUUACUUCCAAAUCCAAAGAAGACAGACAGAAAUUGCUCAAGUUAGAAGUGGACUUUGAACACAAGGCUUCGAGGUUUUCUCAAGAGCAUGAAGAGAUGAACGCUAAACUGGCUAAUCAAGAGUCUCACAAUAGGCAACUUAGACUCAAGCUGGUUGGCUUAACCCAAAGAAUCGAGGAGCUAGAAGAGACCAACAAAAAUCUGCAGAAGGCAGAGGAAGAACUUCAAGAAUUAAGAGAUAAAAUUGCCAAAGGAGAAUGUGGAAACUCUAGCCUCAUGGCAGAAGUGGAAAAUCUUCGAAAGCGUGUGCUUGAAAUGGAAGGUAAAGAUGAGGAGAUCACUAAAACUGAAUCCCAGUGUAGGGAAUUGAGGAAGAAGCUGCAAGAGGAAGAACACCAUAGUAAGGAGCUCAGACUUGAAGUUGAGAAGCUACAGAAGAGAAUGUCUGAACUAGAGAAAUUGGAAGAAGCAUUUAGCAAGAGUAAAUCUGAGUGCACCCAGCUACAUUUAAAUCUGGAGAAAGAAAAGAACUUAACCAAAGACCUGCUAAAUGAAUUGGAGGUGGUCAAGAGUCGAGUUAAAGAAUUGGAAUGUUCUGAAAGUAGAUUGGAAAAGGCUGAAUUAAGCCUAAAAGAUGAUCUUACCAAGUUGAAGUCAUUUACCGUGAUGCUGGUUGAUGAAAGGAAAAAUAUGAUGGAAAAAAUAAAACAAGAAGAGAGAAAAGUGGAUGGACUCAAUAAAAAUUUUAAGGUGGAACAAGGAAAAGUUAUGGAUGUAACUGAAAAACUAAUUGAAGAAAGUAAGAAACUUUUAAAACUAAAAUCUGAAAUGGAGGAAAAAGUAUACAACUUGACAAGAGAAAGAGAUGAGUUGAUAGGCAAAUUGAAAAGUGAAGAAGAAAAAUCCUCUGAAUUAAGCUGCAGUGUUGACUUACUAAAGAAGAGACUUGAUGGUAUAGAGGAAGUGGAAAGAGAAAUAACAAGAGGAAGGUCACGAAAAGGGUCUGAGCUCACCUGCCCGGAAGAUAAUAAGAUUAAGGAACUAACACUUGAAAUUGAGAGACUGAAGAAACGUCUCCAACAAUUGGAAGUGGUCGAAGGGGAUUUGAUGAAGACAGAAGAUGAGUAUGAUCAGCUGGAACAGAAAUUUAGAACUGAGCAGGAUAAGGCUAACUUCCUCUCUCAACAACUAGAGGAGAUCAAGCACCAAAUUGCCAAGAAUAAAGCAAUAGAGAAGGGUGAGGUUGUGAGCCAGGAAGCUGAACUGAGACACAGAUUUCGGUUGGAAGAAGCUAAAAGUCGAGACUUAAAAGCCGAAGUACAAGCUCUUAAAGAGAAGAUUCACGAAUUAAUGAACAAAGAAGAUCAGCUUUCUCAGCUCCAGGUAGAUUAUUCUGUACUUCAACAAAGAUUUAUGGAAGAAGAAAAUAAGAACAAAAACAUGGGGCAGGAGGUUCUCAAUCUGACCAAAGAGUUGGAGCUUUCCAAGCGCUACAGCAGAGCUCUUAGGCCCAGUGUGAAUGGAAGAAGAAUGGUGGAUGUUCCUGUGACGUCAACUGGAGUCCAAACUGAUGCAGUCAGCGGUGAAGCAGCAGAGGAAGAAACGCCAGCUGUAUUCAUACGGAAAUCCUUCCAGGAAGAAAAUCAUAUUAUGAGUAAUCUUCGGCAGGUGGGAUUGAAGAAACCCGUGGAAAGAUCUUCUGUUCUAGACAGGUAUCCUCCAGCAGCAAAUGAGCUCACUAUGAGAAAGUCUUGGAUUCCAUGGAUGAGAAAGAGGGAAAACGGCCCCUCCAUCACUCAGGAGAAAGGGCCCCGAACAAAUUCCAGUCCAGGGCACCCAGGAGAGGUAGUCCUUUCACCAAAGCAGGGCCAGCCCCUGCAUAUUCGAGUGACACCAGACCACGAGAACAGCACUGCGACUUUGGAGAUAACAAGCCCGACAUCUGAAGAAUUUUUUUCUAGUACCACUGUCAUUCCUACCUUAGGGAAUCAGAAACCAAGAAUAACCAUUAUUCCAUCACCAAACGUUAUGCCUCAAAAACAAAAAAGUGGAGAUACUACUCUUGGCCCAGAACGAGCCAUGUCCCCAGUCACAAUUACUACAUUUUCCAGAGAGAAGACUCCAGAAAGUGGAAGAGGCGCAUUUGCAGACAGGCCCACAUCCCCUAUUCAGAUAAUGACGGUGUCUACAUCAGCAGCACCAGCUGAGAUUGCAGUUUCUCCCGAAUCCCAGGAAAUGCCCAUGGGACGGACAAUCCUCAAAGUCACCCCAGAAAAACAGACUGUUCCAACUCCAGUACGGAAAUACAACUCCAAUGCCAAUAUCAUAACCACAGAGGACAAUAAAAUUCACAUUCACUUAGGGUCUCAGUUUAAACGGUCCCCUGGGACUUCAGGUGAAGGAGUCAGUCCAGUUAUUACUGUCCGACCAGUAAACGUGACAGCCGAAAAGGAGGUUUCCACCGGCACUGUCCUUCGCUCUCCCAGGAAUCACCUCUCCUCACGGCCUGGUGCAAGCAAAGUGACGAGCACUAUCACCAUAACACCGGUCACAACGUCAUCUGCUCGAGGAACCCAGUCAGUGUCAGGACAAGACGGGUCAUCCCAGCGGCCUACACCCACCCGCAUUCCUAUGUCAAAAGGUAUGAAAGCAGGAAAGCCAGUAGUGGCAGCCCCAGGAGCAGGAAAUCUGACCAAAUUCGAGCCUCGAGCUGAGACUCAGUCUAUGAAAAUAGAGCUGAAGAAAUCUGCAGCCAGCAGCACCACCUCUCUCGGAGGGGGGAAGGGCUGAGGGCAGUGGCUAAGGGGAAAGCAUCAUCAUUCACCAGUUACGAAUGAACUCCAGAUGAAAUGGUAAACCAAGCACAUACUGGGUGUGUGUACGACCUCUGAAUCCCUAUUGAAUGGACAGCCCUCAAUCAUGACUAAGGUCCUCCAUGCUACUGAUCACUACUGGAAAUAUUUUACUACUUCCAGUGAUUUUUUUUUAAGGAUAUAAUGUAAAAAGCUGAAAAUGGCCUUGCUGAUAAUAUGAAAAUAUGUAGCAAGAGCAAUUCAAUCUAUGUGCCAAAAGAAAUUUCUUUUUGCAAAGCUUUCAGGUCUAUGGGCACAUGCUGUAUAACUUAUAUUUUAUAAUACAUUUUGUAAUGUGAUUUUUUUUGCUAAAGUGUUUCCCUUUUUCAUAGUCUCUGGCACAUAUAUCUAUGGAAUACGCUGUCAGUUCUUCAAAGUACUGGUAUUGUUGCAUUCAAAAUGGUAAUCUAUAAUUAUUUUCUUUUUAUCAAUUUGUUAAUUCUGAAAAAAAGAAAGUACAACUAUAUUUCCUGAGGUAAAUUCAAGAGGUAAAACUUAGAAGCAGGAGACUCUGGAAGAGGUUUUACUAUUGCUUGUACAAUGCUAUGGUUCUGAUCAUGGUUCAAUGCUAACAAAUAAUGCUCUGACUUAAAAGCUUAAUUUUAAAUACUAAAAAUCAGUUUCUAAAGUUGCUCUUUCUGGUGUUCUGGGCCAAAAACCUUGGAUGAAAUGAUUUUUAUAUAGAACAAAUUCAUAAAAGGAGAUGUACCAGUUUAACCAGUAAGGGCAAUAAGAACAGCUUCGACUGACAGUUCAAUUAUACUUCUGAUUGCAUUAUUUACUUGUAUGUAUAAGACUUAUAAUAAGGACUGUGAAAUAAAGAUAGUUCUCACAAUCUAAUCCAAUCAAAACUUGAAUAUAAAAACAGACCUAAAAUGUCAGGAUCUUUUUUAAAAAAUAAGACUGGGCAUGGUGGGUCGUGCCUGUAAUCCCAGCACUUUGGGAGGCCAAGGCGGGAGAAUCGCUUAAGCCCAGGAGUUCAGGAUCAGCCUGGGCAACACAGUGAGAGUCUUAAAAAAAAAAAAAAAAAAAAAAAAAAAAAGAAGUUAGCUGGGCCUGAUUGCACGUGCCUGUAGUCCUAGCUACUUGGGAGUCUGAGGUGGGAGGAUCACUUGAGCCCAGGAGAUGGAGGCUGCAGGGAGCCAUGAUUGUGUCACUGUACUCCAGCCUGGGUGACAGAGUGAGACUCUGUCUCAAAACAAAGACAAACCCACACACACACAAAAACCCCCAAAACCCAGAAGGAAAAAGUAGUACAAGAAAUCUCAGGAUCGAUAACUUUUUUCCCCUUGAUUUUGAAAGAUUUUCGUAACUACAGGUAGGUCAGAGAAUAUAUUCUUUGAAGAUAAAAAGCACAACGUGCAUUACUCAAAUCUCAACGUCAGAGCUACUGUUGAAUUUAGGUUUAUGUGAAAAUGUGCAUCUAAAGUCUACUUGAAACCCUGGUAAUAUACUUUUUUUUUUAAAGACUGUUAAUAUGGACAUGUUUUUAGUAAGGUCUUUAAAGAUAACUUUAAAGAUAAAUUAAGAGUUGACACAUCAGUUUCUGAAUGUGGAAGUCAUUUAUCAUGUAACUUUACUGAAAUUAAAGAGAGAAUGCUUCUGAGUGUCACAAGGAUAACUAAAAGCCACACAAGGAGGACUGCUGGCCCAUUUCUCUAGUUCACAGGUUGUGCUCAGCUUUAGAAGCCCACACACGGGCAUCCAAACUGAGUCUCUGGAAUAGAAAAAUUAAUGAUGGACUUCCUCCCCUAUGUAACCUUGGAAGGUUUUAAGUUACACCUUGGGGAAUUGGCAAAUCAUUUUCAACAUGUAUUAUAAAUUAUAUGAUGUUAAAAUUAUUUUUAAUUUUUUAAAGUAAAAGAAAUGUUACAGUAGGCUUGCCAUAGCUUGAAUGAUUGUGAAAACAUCACAUAAACUUCCAGAAUUUUGGUUACUAAGAAAACUGGAGUGUGUAUGUGUGAUUUUUUAGAAUUGUUACUGGGUUUUGUUUUCUGAAAAUGUUGACUGUAAUGACAUUUUCAAUUAGAAAAGUGUUUUAGUUAGUACUGUUAUAUUUUUUGACUCACAGUUAAGUAUCCUAUUUGCCAAUGUUUGUACCUCUGAUGGCAAAAUUAUUUGAUAUAUUAGAUUAGUAUUUGAAGCAAAUAACUUUCUCAACUUGUGGGAAUUUUAUUAUACUAAUAGUGAAAAUGUUAGAGGAUAAGAUUUUAAAUACUUCUUGAUUUAAAUUAAAAUACUAUAAGAAAUGUAUGUAUAUUUGGAUUUGAAGAUUUUUUUUCCCCAGAUUUAUAAUGAAUUUGGAACUUACAAGAACAAUGAGGAUGAUGGUGCAAUCAGAGUCAUUUAGAUAGAUGGUGAGCCUUUUCUGUCCAUGCUAUGAUUAAGUCCUCUGUUUAAACCCAAAUGCAAUCUGAGUGACACAUGAAUAAAAUUAAUUAGAUUAAUUUUGAAAUAAGAGAAUAUGCAAAAUUAACCAAAAAACCCCCAGAAAACACUGGUCAUCUCCUUCUCUAAUGAAUAAGGAAAUAAGAUCAUAAAUAGUCCCAUCUCAACAUGCAUAUGCAAUUGAAAAAACUGCCCUCACAGGCAAUCCUGGCACAAUCCUAGGCUCAUAAAAUUUCUCUAUCUUUUCUUGUAAAUAAGUCUCCAGUCAUCAUUCUAAAUGGGAAUCAUUUUUAAUGAAAUAAUUAUAACUGUUUUCUGAAAUAUAAUCAUAAUCAGUGUUUCUAGUUCAAGGUACAAUUGAACUAAUCCAUAAUUUUACCCUUUUCUUUUUGAUAAGAGAGUGUUUCAUGAGGGUAUCUUUGGUAGAGAUCUUUUCUCAAGUAUUUUAUAAAAUAUUCGAGUUUGAUGAAGAUGGUAGAUAAAUACACCAGCUGUCAGAUGCCUAUAAUUUUCACAAAAUGUGAAGAAUUCAUUGUAUCUUAGGAUGACCAUAAAAAAAUUCAUGGUGUGGAAUCUCUAAGCAUUAAUAGAGACAACAGCGCUACUGCAGUAAUACACAGCUACUACAAAUCAGUGGCAGAGCAAGAAUAAGUGGUGUAUCAGGCAAUGUGAAGUUUUUGCCUUUUCUCCUAAUGCUGUGGUUGAGUUUUCCUGGAAAUGAAGGAAAAAAACAUAGCAAAAGUAGGGUGUGUUAAUGAAUCUGAUGAGCAACAAGUCUAAAAAUAGCAAAAGUGCAAAAUGGAAGUUAAAAAACGCAACUGGCACCUGAAGCAUAUUUCCCCUUCUUUAUCUCCAGUGCUAUGCCUCUGCUAAAAAUAUGAAUCACAAAGCAAAGGAAAAAGAGAAAAAAAGUGUUGUAAUACAGUAAAAAUCACUAUAAUAAAAGUUUAUAAGAAUUGAGUUUUUUGGAAUUGACUUUGGCCUAGUAACCAUUAGUAUUUCUUAAUUUUUCAGCAUUUAUUCCAUACUAAUGUGAUAACAACUGUGUGUGUUACCUAGAGAAAAUGCUGUAGAUCCACACAUUUGAACAGAAAUGUUUAUCGAUGCCAUAACGUGAUACAUUUGCUUUCCGGUGUUGUUUUUUGUUUAUAUUAUUUAGGGAAAUUUUACCUUACCAUCACAGAUUUUGUUACUUUAAUAAUGCAGAACUAUAUUUAUUUAAUCUAGAUUUUGUUUUAAAAUUAUCAAGUGUUAGCUUUUACAAAUAAGAGGCUUAUAAUGUGGCCAGAUAUUCUUAGAAUUCUUUUAGGUCUAAGUGUUUUCAAAACUUUAAGAAAUACAUUCUAUUUUUGCACCAUUUAAAAUUUUGUUUCCUUUUAAGUUUUAUUAAGUACACGAGAAGUUUAUUAUUUUUCAUUGAAUCCAAGUGAAUUUAUGGAUAUGUACUUAUCUUUUAUAUGAAUGUAAUAGCUUGCUUUCAGUUCCUCACAGGUCAUUGAAAUUAUUUAACCAAUGAAAACAUUCUCUGUUACUUCCAAAGUCAACUAUGUUUAUCAAAAUCUCACUAGUGUGAGAAAAAUAACAAGUGUAAUAUUAAAGCAUUGUGCAAUAUCUUGAGUUGGAACAUAAUAUUCAGAAAAUUAAAAUCAUUUAAAAUGA